GAAGCCGGCGUGCGGCGCGGCGCGGCGGGCGCGGAGCGAGCGGGCGGGCGAGCGCCUCCGUCCCCGGAUGUGAGCUCCGGCUGCCCGCGGUCCCGAGCCAGCGGCGGCGCGGGCGGCGGCGGCGGGCACCGGGCACCGCGGCGGGCGGGCAGACGGGCGGGCAUGGGGGGAGCGCCGAGCGGCCCCGGCGGCCGGGCCGGCAUCACCGCGGCGUCUCUCCGCUAGAGGAGGGGACAAGCCAGUUCUCCUUUGCAGCAAAAAAUUACAUGUAUAUAUUAUUAAGAUAAUAUAUACAUUGGAUUUUAUUUUUUUAAAAAGUUUAUUUUGCUCCAUUUUUGAAAAAGAGAGAGCUUGGGUGGCGAGCGGUUUUUUUUUUAAAUCAAUUAUCCUUAUUUUCUGUUAUUUGUCCCCGUCCCUCCCCACCCCCCUGCUGAAGCGAGAAUAAGGGCAGGGACCGCGGCUCCUACCUCUUGGUGAUCCCCUUCCCCAUUCCGCCCCCGCCUCAACGCCCAGCACAGUGCCCUGCACACAGUAGUCGCUCAAUAAAUGUUCGUGGAUGAUGAUGAUGAUGAUGAUGAAAAAAAUGCAGCAUCAACGGCAGCAGCAAGCGGACCACGCGAACGAGGCAAACUAUGCAAGAGGCACCAGACUUCCUCUUUCUGGUGAAGGACCAACUUCUCAGCCGAAUAGCUCCAAGCAAACUGUCCUGUCUUGGCAAGCUGCAAUCGAUGCUGCUAGACAGGCCAAGGCUGCCCAAACUAUGAGCACCUCUGCACCCCCACCUGUAGGAUCUCUCUCCCAAAGAAAACGUCAGCAAUACGCCAAGAGCAAAAAACAGGGUAACUCGUCCAACAGCCGACCUGCCCGCGCCCUUUUCUGUUUAUCACUCAAUAACCCCAUCCGAAGAGCCUGCAUUAGUAUAGUGGAAUGGAAACCAUUUGACAUAUUUAUAUUAUUGGCUAUUUUUGCCAAUUGUGUGGCCUUAGCUAUUUACAUCCCAUUCCCUGAAGAUGAUUCUAAUUCAACAAAUCAUAACUUGGAAAAAGUAGAAUAUGCCUUCCUGAUUAUUUUUACAGUCGAGACAUUUUUGAAGAUUAUAGCGUAUGGAUUAUUGCUACAUCCUAAUGCUUAUGUUAGGAAUGGAUGGAAUUUACUGGAUUUUGUUAUAGUAAUAGUAGGAUUGUUUAGUGUAAUUUUGGAACAAUUAACCAAAGAAACAGAAGGCGGGAACCACUCAAGCGGCAAAUCUGGAGGCUUUGAUGUCAAAGCCCUCCGUGCCUUUCGAGUGUUGCGACCACUUCGACUAGUGUCAGGAGUGCCCAGUUUACAAGUUGUCCUGAACUCCAUUAUAAAAGCCAUGGUUCCCCUCCUUCACAUAGCCCUUUUGGUAUUAUUUGUAAUCAUAAUCUAUGCUAUUAUAGGAUUGGAACUUUUUAUUGGAAAAAUGCACAAAACAUGUUUUUUUGCUGACUCAGAUAUCGUAGCUGAAGAGGACCCAGCUCCAUGUGCGUUCUCAGGGAAUGGACGCCAGUGUACUGCCAAUGGCACGGAAUGUAGGAGUGGCUGGGUUGGCCCGAACGGAGGCAUCACCAACUUUGAUAACUUUGCCUUUGCCAUGCUUACUGUGUUUCAGUGCAUCACCAUGGAGGGCUGGACAGAUGUGCUCUACUGGGUAAAUGAUGCGAUAGGAUGGGAAUGGCCAUGGGUGUAUUUUGUUAGUCUGAUCAUCCUUGGCUCAUUUUUCGUCCUUAACCUGGUUCUUGGUGUCCUUAGUGGAGAAUUCUCAAAGGAAAGAGAGAAGGCAAAAGCACGGGGAGAUUUCCAGAAGCUCCGGGAGAAGCAGCAGCUGGAGGAGGAUCUAAAGGGCUACUUGGAUUGGAUCACCCAAGCUGAGGACAUCGAUCCGGAGAAUGAGGAAGAAGGAGGAGAGGAAGGCAAACGAAAUACUAGCAUGCCCACCAGCGAGACUGAGUCUGUGAACACAGAGAACGUCAGCGGUGAAGGCGAGAACCGAGGCUGCUGUGGAAGUCUCUGUCAAGCCAUCUCAAAAUCCAAACUCAGCCGACGCUGGCGUCGCUGGAACCGAUUCAAUCGCAGAAGAUGUAGGGCCGCCGUGAAGUCUGUCACGUUUUACUGGCUGGUUAUCGUCCUGGUGUUUCUGAACACCUUAACCAUUUCCUCUGAGCACUACAAUCAGCCAGAUUGGUUGACACAGAUUCAAGAUAUUGCCAACAAAGUCCUCUUGGCUCUGUUCACCUGCGAGAUGCUGGUAAAAAUGUACAGCUUGGGCCUCCAAGCAUAUUUCGUCUCUCUUUUCAACCGGUUUGAUUGCUUCGUGGUGUGUGGUGGAAUCACUGAGACGAUCUUGGUGGAACUGGAAAUCAUGUCUCCCCUGGGGAUCUCUGUGUUUCGGUGUGUGCGCCUCUUAAGAAUCUUCAAAGUGACCAGGCACUGGACUUCCCUGAGCAACUUAGUGGCAUCCUUAUUAAACUCCAUGAAGUCCAUCGCUUCGCUGUUGCUUCUGCUUUUUCUCUUCAUUAUCAUCUUUUCCUUGCUUGGGAUGCAGCUGUUUGGCGGCAAGUUUAAUUUUGAUGAAACGCAAACCAAGCGGAGCACCUUUGACAAUUUCCCUCAAGCACUUCUCACAGUGUUCCAGAUCCUGACAGGCGAAGACUGGAAUGCUGUGAUGUACGAUGGCAUCAUGGCUUACGGGGGCCCAUCCUCUUCAGGAAUGAUCGUCUGCAUCUACUUCAUCAUCCUCUUCAUUUGUGGUAACUAUAUUCUACUGAAUGUCUUCUUGGCCAUCGCUGUAGACAAUUUGGCUGAUGCUGAAAGUCUGAACACUGCUCAGAAAGAAGAAGCGGAAGAAAAGGAGAGGAAAAAGAUUGCCAGAAAAGAGAGCCUAGAAAAUAAAAAGAACAACAAACCAGAAGUCAACCAGAUAGCCAACAGUGACAACAAGGUUACAAUUGAUGACUAUAGAGAAGAGGAUGAAGACAAGGACCCCUAUCCGCCUUGCGAUGUGCCAGUAGGGGAAGAGGAAGAGGAAGAGGAGGAGGAUGAACCUGAGGUUCCUGCCGGACCCCGUCCUCGAAGGAUCUCGGAGUUGAACAUGAAGGAAAAAAUUGCCCCCAUCCCUGAAGGGAGCGCUUUCUUCAUUCUUAGCAAGACCAACCCGAUCCGCGUAGGCUGCCACAAGCUCAUCAACCACCACAUCUUCACCAACCUCAUCCUUGUCUUCAUCAUGCUGAGCAGCGCUGCCCUGGCCGCAGAGGACCCCAUCCGCAGCCACUCCUUCCGGAACACGAUACUGGGUUACUUUGACUAUGCCUUCACAGCCAUCUUUACUGUUGAGAUCCUGUUGAAGAUGACAACUUUUGGAGCUUUCCUCCACAAAGGGGCCUUCUGCAGGAACUACUUCAAUUUGCUGGAUAUGCUGGUGGUUGGGGUGUCUCUGGUGUCAUUUGGGAUUCAAUCCAGUGCCAUCUCCGUUGUGAAGAUUCUGAGGGUCUUAAGGGUCCUGCGUCCCCUCAGGGCCAUCAACAGAGCAAAAGGACUUAAGCACGUGGUCCAGUGCGUCUUCGUGGCCAUCCGGACCAUCGGCAACAUCAUGAUCGUCACCACCCUCCUGCAGUUCAUGUUUGCCUGUAUCGGGGUCCAGUUGUUCAAGGGGAAGUUCUAUCGCUGUACGGAUGAAGCCAAAAGUAACCCUGAAGAAUGCAGGGGACUUUUCAUCCUCUACAAGGAUGGGGAUGUUGACAGUCCUGUGGUCCGUGAACGGAUCUGGCAAAACAGUGAUUUCAACUUCGACAACGUCCUCUCUGCUAUGAUGGCGCUCUUCACAGUCUCCACGUUUGAGGGCUGGCCUGCGUUGCUGUAUAAAGCCAUCGACUCGAAUGGAGAGAACAUCGGCCCAAUCUACAACCACCGCGUGGAGAUCUCCAUCUUCUUCAUCAUCUACAUCAUCAUUGUAGCUUUCUUCAUGAUGAACAUCUUUGUGGGCUUUGUCAUCGUUACAUUUCAGGAACAAGGAGAAAAAGAGUAUAAGAACUGUGAGCUGGACAAAAAUCAGCGUCAGUGUGUUGAAUACGCCUUGAAAGCACGUCCCUUGCGGAGAUACAUCCCCAAAAACCCCUACCAGUACAAGUUCUGGUACGUGGUGAACUCUUCGCCUUUCGAAUACAUGAUGUUUGUCCUCAUCAUGCUCAACACACUCUGCUUGGCCAUGCAGCACUACGAGCAGUCCAAGAUGUUCAAUGAUGCCAUGGACAUUCUGAACAUGGUCUUCACCGGGGUGUUCACCGUCGAGAUGGUUUUGAAAGUCAUCGCAUUUAAGCCUAAGGGGUAUUUUAGUGACGCCUGGAACACGUUUGACUCCCUCAUCGUAAUCGGCAGCAUUAUAGACGUGGCCCUCAGCGAAGCAGACAACUCUGAAGAGAGCAAUAGAAUCUCCAUCACCUUUUUCCGUCUUUUCCGAGUGAUGCGAUUGGUGAAGCUUCUCAGCAGGGGGGAAGGCAUCCGGACAUUGCUGUGGACUUUUAUUAAGUCCUUUCAGGCGCUCCCGUAUGUGGCCCUCCUCAUAGCCAUGCUGUUCUUCAUCUAUGCGGUCAUUGGCAUGCAGAUGUUUGGGAAAGUUGCCAUGAGAGAUAACAACCAGAUCAAUAGGAACAAUAACUUCCAGACGUUUCCCCAGGCGGUGCUGCUGCUCUUCAGGUGUGCAACAGGUGAGGCCUGGCAGGAGAUCAUGCUGGCCUGUCUCCCAGGGAAGCUCUGUGACCCUGAGUCAGAUUACAACCCCGGGGAGGAGUAUACAUGUGGGAGCAACUUUGCCAUUGUCUAUUUCAUCAGUUUUUACAUGCUCUGUGCAUUUCUGAUCAUCAAUCUGUUUGUGGCUGUCAUCAUGGAUAAUUUCGACUAUCUGACCCGGGACUGGUCUAUUUUGGGGCCUCACCAUUUAGAUGAAUUCAAAAGAAUAUGGUCAGAAUAUGACCCUGAGGCAAAGGGAAGGAUAAAACACCUUGAUGUGGUCACUCUGCUUCGACGCAUCCAGCCUCCCCUGGGGUUUGGGAAGUUAUGUCCACACAGGGUAGCGUGCAAGAGAUUAGUUGCCAUGAACAUGCCUCUCAACAGUGACGGGACAGUCAUGUUUAAUGCAACCCUGUUUGCUUUGGUUCGAACGGCUCUUAAGAUCAAGACCGAAGGGAACCUGGAGCAAGCUAAUGAAGAACUUCGGGCUGUGAUAAAGAAAAUUUGGAAGAAAACCAGCAUGAAAUUACUUGACCAAGUUGUCCCUCCAGCUGGUGAUGAUGAGGUAACCGUGGGGAAGUUCUAUGCCACUUUCCUGAUACAGGACUACUUUAGGAAAUUCAAGAAACGGAAAGAACAAGGACUGGUGGGAAAGUACCCUGCGAAGAACACCACAAUUGCCCUACAGAUGCUUGAACGGAUGCUUUAGAAUUUUCUGCCUGAGCUACGGCACCAAGCUGGUUAGUCGGAAGGCGUUUGUGGCUAAGGCCUUGAAAGGGAAAAGUCUCAAGUGGGCUUAUUUCUACUGAAACAGCAUUUCAGAAGAAAUGCAGGAAAAAGCAGACCCAAGGCCCCAGGGAGACCCCUUCCAAGCAAAGCACUCCUCCGGAAGGUGGAAGCGGGGCCGUGGCUCAUCUGCGGAGCCAGGGCUGCCUGUCGCGGACGUUGCUCACGGUGGUUCUUUUUCGUGAAAGGGAACGUACAAAGCUUAACAGUUUUCCCUUCCAAGCAGAGACUCAGAGAAAGGGAAAGAGUGAGAGAGAGCAAAGGAGGGGGGCAGCUGCCCCACAGAGAAAUGAAAUGAACACAACUUCCUGAUGCUGGCCAGUAAAACAAAAAAUUAAAAAUAAAAAUAAAAAGAUUAAGCAGACCUGCCUAAGGUGGGUAUCUGACUCCAUUCCAAAGUCCUGCAUCCCUAGUUUGCCCGAACUCCCAAAGACUGACAGGCCCCUCGGCGCUGAGCUGACAGAGUUCCUUUUGUAUGCCAGUCCGCCAUGACCUCCUGAGCGUCCGGCCCUGCUCUCUGCAGAGACCCAGUCCAGAAUACAGUGAGAAGUGGACAGGCCAGGAAGCUCAGAUACACCCAUUGAAACUAACACAUACACCCGCAUGCCAAAACCAAUCCAGGCAACACCUCAGGUUCCAUCUUAACGUGUCCACAGGAAACACCACCACACCCAAACCUCAUCUAACAUUGUCCGUCUUUAAUUCGUGCUCAGAGCCAGUCUGGGGAUGCCUCUUUGGAAGCAGUGUGGUCUAGUUUCAAGGACACUGGGAGUCAGGGAACCUGGGUUCUAGUCCCAGUUUCAGCAUUCACUUGCUGCGUGACCUUGGGCAAGACACUUAACCUCUCUGUGCCUCAGUUUCCCCCAUCUGUAAAAUGGGGUUAAUAAUGUCGACCUACCUCACAGGGCUGUUGUGAGGAAUAGCUAAGUGAUUGUAAAGCACUUUGAACGUAUAAUUGCUUAUUAAGACUACAACAAUAAUAAUAUCAUAUGCCUGUUUACUACCAGAACUUUAAGAAAUUCUUGUUUUCCUUUGAUCUCUUUUCUGUUCUGUACCAUACUUACCCAUUGAGAAGGAAAAUUCCCCCCUUUUAAAGAAAUCUAGGCAAUGCACAAAGAUGUCAACAGAGGUAACCCUGCAGGUUGCAUUUUCACAUCUUAAGAAUAGCAGAUUUUUGCCCAAGAUGUUGGUCGAUAAGGGUGUCUGAUCUUGAAUUCUCAGCUGAUUCCAAGUGGUGGUUGGAGUCUGUACAUCUGAUGCUGAGCCCAAGACACCCAAAGUGGCCAGUUUGGGUUUUAAGAUCAACAUUCAAAGUAGCCAUAGUGCAGAGGUAAUGCAGAAGAAUCUAAAAAAAUUGAAGUAUCUGAAGUGUAUAGAGAAAAGAAGGGCUUAUGAGCCCCUUUCACCUGCCCUGAUGUGUACAGGCUGGAAGCUGUGUGUGUGUGCGAGUGCGUGUGUAUGUAUGUGGGGUGUGCGGAGACAGGGGAAGAGAGAGCCAGCAAACUCUGGGGGGCCCUAUUCCUGUAGAAGUGGACACCCUUCCAAGCAUCCUGGGAGGGCAGGAGUCCCAAAGGCUAGGCAGAGGGUGGGAGCAAUGUCACCAGUGGGAAGUAUGCUUUCUGCAGGCUUGUCCUAGGUGUGACUGACAGGGUCAGUCCCAGCCUCAGGGUCUUUUCCAGUGGUGUCUUUUGUGCCUAUGACAUUUGCCCUUGGCUGCAGUCCUCACUGUACCGAGAGGUCUAACCUACCUGGACUUCAGUGGACCUGCUGUCCUCAUUAUGGAAAUGGGCCUAGCUCCCGACUCUGCCCCCAUGUGUAUAAGUGUGCAGACUAGUUAACAUCCAGGAGCUCACAGUAGGUGUUGUGGGUUCUCACAGCACAGUCCACAGGGCCCAAGGGCAGGUUUGACUGCUUCGUGCUGCACCACAUGGUGAUGUGGGGGAUGGGGUAGAAAGCCAGGAACACUCCAGUGUGGCCAGGCCACUUGUCAAGAUGUUGAAGCACAGCUGCACCUGGUAUCAACCGCUGUUACCCUAGCACCUGAGUCUCCUUCCCCACUGCCAGCAGCCCAGCCCCUCCUGAGACUGCUCUGUGACCCAGCAGCUACAGGUCUAGUGCCUGGCAUUGCAGGGAGCCUCCAGGACCCUGCUGUGAUCCAAAGGCCCACUUCUGCUCUGAUUGGGCAGCACCUGGGUAUAUUAAGUUAUAAGAAUUUAUGAAGAAUGUGAUGUAUCGUCCCUGAAAGGGAAGCCCGUCAGUCCUGUGGGGGUCCGUCAGUCCCUCUGUCUGUCUUUGACCCACCCGACGUUGAGUUGAUUCAGUGCUGAAGGAUGGCACGUGCCUACCCCCUGUAUGUGUCACUCUGUCUCAGAGGGCCGGUGUGACCGACCUUCUAGAUCCAAGAUUCCAUACACUCAGGCCUCGGCAGAAAGGCCCCAAGCGAUUCAAGUGGGCGGCGUUUCCAUGUGCCUUCUCCACGCUCCUCAAAUAAGUAAAAACUGACAAGUGACCACUUUCUAGAUGGGACUUAGGGAGUGAUUUAAAUGGAACAAGAGAGUCUUCUCCACUUGGGCCUGGCUGUGUUGCUGGGGAAUGGCAUUGGCUAAGGUUGGUAGCCAAGGCCAGCUUAGGAAAGACAGCCAGGAAUCAGGAAAGCUGCUUCCAGCUUCAACUCAAAAGGGAAAGAAGGCUUCCUGAAACUUGAUUUGCAGUCAAACUGCAGAGACACCGCUGUCGUUUCUCUUAAAGCCUUGGCAGAGAAGUGUAGCUUCUAGUGUAGUCAAAGUUGUGAGAGACGACUCAAGUUCAUUAUUUAGAAUCUUCACAGACACACACAGCAAACUUGGCACCCCCAACACCAGCAUCCAUAGGCUAAACUCUUCAGCUCCUGGAUAGAAGAUGAGAGGCAGGCCAGUAUACAUUGUAGGGAGGCUCUUCUCAAAUAGCUUAUACUGUUUAACAACCCAAUUAAAAAUUAAUCCACAGGACUAUUGGGUACUACAUUCUAUACUCUUUCUGAAAGUGGGGAGAUCUCAUUCCUUUGAGAAUAAUAAUUAUGUUCAGGAGUCUUUGAGAAGAAAGACUGCAAAGAAGUUAAGUGAUGUGACGUAGUAGUAAAAGGUGGUAAUUAUCGUGGCUUGUUAUUUAGUACCAUUCACCUAGUGUCCUUUGGCAGCCCAAUUGUGUCAUGAUUAGAUGAUCUGUGCGAAGGAGCUGGCUAAGACUUACUAACAGUUCUAGGGUGGGUAGAAACCCAGGUGAGUUCAUUCUCCUUGGCACCUCUUAGACCUAAGGGACACAGCUGUUUGAGAUCUUGGAAGGGCACAUAAUUCUAAGGCAUGGUGAAGGCAACCCAUUCAGACGUCCCAAAGGCUGGCUCAGGGAAGCCAUAGGAAGGCCAUUUCUUCCAAGAGUGGAGAAAGGUCCACAGAAGAGUGGGAAUCCUAGAUGGGGUAAAAAAGUCUACACCUGAGGAAAAAGUAGUAGUGCCUGUUGGAGGAUAGAUUGAUCAGCAGUUAUCAAACUUUUUGGUCUUCGGACCCUUUUAUACUCUACAUUAUUGAAGACCCUUGUGUGUCAAUAUUUACUGUCUUAGAAAUUAAAACGGAGCAGUUUUUAAAACAAGAACAUGCAAGCACAAAGACGCCAGGGUGAUGACAUCAUGCAUCAGGCAGCCUUUGAAAACCUCACUGUGCUCUCAUGAGAGGAUGAGAGUGUUGAAGGCAAAGAACAUCCUUAUGUUAUGCAAAUCACAGUGACCUCAUGGACCCCUGACAGUGUCUUGGGAUGCCCCAAGGUCCCCAGAACACACCUGAGAACUGCUUUGGGGGAAUGCUACUAGGUCCCCCUAAAGGCAGAGGGUGCUGGAGCCUUUUAAUCAUCUCCCUUGUUAAAGAGGCUCCUGUGCAGUGGCACUGCCCUAACUGGAGCCCUUCUCCCCCUCCAGCCCCUUCCCAGUCUCAGCCCACUCCCCGGAGGCAUGGAGCUGCCUGUGUCCCCAUUCGUCUAGCAUGGCCGAGUCUUGCGGCCUGUGCUGAUCUGCAGGUGUGAUGGUCUGAAUCAGGGCAGGAUAGAAAGUGUUUUUAAAAAUCAGCUCCCCUAAGUGCACAACUGGGACCAAGGAUGUGUGCCAAACAGGAUCCGUUUCAGGGAUAACUUUUGAUCAUUUGUCAUCUCCAUGCUGACUUAGGAAUAUAAGAGCUCUGCUAGGGUAGUCAAAAGAGGGUUAGCCUUGAUCAGGUGGCACCCCACAGUCGUGACUAUAGGUGAGUAAGUGUGUGAUUCAGACUCCAAUCCAGCGUUCUUUCCCAGUAGGUGCAGUGACUUUGCCUGGGUGGUGGUUGAGGUGGGGAGUUUGGGAGAGGUAAGGCAGCCCAGUGUCACAGGAAGAACAGGCUUAGGGGCCAAGAGUCCUCACUGAGCCUUUGACUCAUUUGGGCACAUAAUUUAACCACAUGGGAAUAACUUUGGCUCUCCCUUCCUCCCAGAAUCUAGUGGAAUAUUUGUAUGUAAGCUCACAAUGACUGGUAUAAAGAUGCUAUCAGAACAGAAGUUGUGUUUUACAGCUUCUGCUAAGCCUAAACUUUACAGAAUGCUCUAUUAUCAGGAAACUGGCAAGACUUUUUUUGAUUCGGUUGUUAAAAUUACAACGAAUCAGAUUCCUGAUUGCACCAAGAAUCAAGGUGGAACUGAAACGGAGAGCUCUCAGAUUGUGUGCAGGCAAAGGUCAUAUUUUAGAUAAUUUCUUUAAAGUUUCCUUUAUCUUUCCAAGUGAUGGGAAUAGCGCAACCCCUAGGGGAGCUUGUGGGGGUCAUGUUACCCCUGACUUUUCAGUGAGGGUUGGAAUCACUGUGGAUGACUAACAGAGCGCCAGGAUCCCAACCCUUUAUAUCUGACACAAGGACCAUUCACAAUGGACACAAAGGCUGCCAUCACAUUAUCCCUGGAGGAGAGUGGUGACAAAAUAAGGGGUGUGCCCACGUGUGAUGUGCUGAGGAGGCGGACGGCAGCUUGCAGAUGAGCAGGUUUAUUCCAUAAGAACUUAAUCUCAUUCUGUUUUCUAAUGGAACUAGUCUAAAAAGGUCCCCUCUCAUUGGGUAUAGACUGAAUCCUGCUAAAGGGUUAACCAGAACUUGUCACCAGCGAGACGACUGUGUGCAGGGCCAGCCUAGGCUGAGUGCAGCCUGCCUGUGAUGGGGAACAGGCUCUGCCAGGCAGGGUUCUUUGGCUGGAGUCUCAAAGCCUGGCGCUUGUAUCCUGAAGAUGAAUGGCCUGGCCCAGUCCCGACUAGAGACAUGCAUCUCUUAUCUCCACUGCUACAGCGUAGGUCCAGGGCGGGGCUCUGGGCACUUGUGCAUGCUUGCUGUGGCGCUGUGAGGGCUGGCAGAUGGCUGGUGUGUCUGAUGGAGCUAGCUUAGGGACACAGGCAGCAAAAGCAUUGCAAAUGCAUCUAGGCAGGAGAAACUUAACCCUAAAAGUGGGCAGGAGAAAGAAAGGUAAAUGGGUGUUCAUAUUUGAUGUCAAAAUGUCAUCAUAUUAUGCUAUUCAGAAGUGUUUUGAGACAUUUUAGUUUUUUUUGGUAACUUAAUCAUUCAAUAGAAUAUCUAUGAAAUUCCAACUAAAUGGUGUCUAAAAUUUUAAGCAGCAGUCUACAGGCAAAGCGCCAACAUUUCUUUUCUAAAAAUUAUUUAUGAUAACAUCUAGCAUUUUAAAAUCAACCAGAAACUAGGCUUGAUUCUGUUUAAUAUUUUAUAAGAUUGGACAUCUUAAAAUAAGUCAAUAAUGUUUAUAUUUUAUAGCAACUCUGUGUUUCUUCAAAACCAUAUUUCUGCUGUGAUGUUAAUGGAAUGACUUUAUAUGGCUUUAAUUGUGUUGGUUUAAGUGCUAAUGACCACUUUUCAAAUUAAAAUAGUAUUUUGCUGAUAGAGGUAGACACAGAUAUGAGAUAUGAAAGAAUAGAUAAUUUUACUGUUUGUAAAGUGUUUAUCCCAAGAAAAAAAAUGUUCUUUUUUUUAGGGCUGUGGAAAAGUAAUUUUUUCAAGAGUCUAAGAUAGUUUUCUGUAUUUCUGGGGAUUGGAACUUGUGCCUAUGGAAUUUUGGGAGCAGCCUAAGCUACCUUUUAGCUUGAUAUGUGUGCUAGAAAAACUUCAUUACCAUGUUUUGUGAUAUGUAAUAAAUUCAGGGUGCUGUGCUUAAGCUUCAUGUCAAUUCUAGUUUGGGAACAUCUGUUUCCCUCACUCCCAGUCGUGGGGGACAGCCUGACCUGGCCCUACCCAGAACACAUGUGAAAAAGUAGAGUCAGUCCCUGACUCUUAUGAGGUCUGUUUUUUCCUGCCUGGAACAAGCAGAAUAUAAUCAUGAUUUCUGACUCUCUGCUUCUGUGUCUGGGAAGAGCGAUUCUUCUCUCCUCCUCUAAUGUCUCUUUAAUAAAUAUGUUGUCAUUAUUUGUCUUUGGAAGUGGCAACUUGGGCCACCUUUCAACCUUCUCCAUGAUUUAUGUUGCAAACAAAUUCUCUGUCCCAUGUCUGUUCAUUGCACUAUCUUGUCGACUAAAUCCUAAUCUUGUGUAUCACUGAAGAUGUGCUGGAGACAGUUUUUGUUUCUAUUAUGCAAUUAUGUUAUAUGUGUAUUUCAGUGAAAUGUCAACCCGUCAACAGAGGAUGAUGUUAAAAAUUAUCCAAAUAAAUAGUUUUCUAUUUCUUUUAA